GGUCGCGACUGCGCGCGCAGGGCCUGAGCGGGCGCCGGAGGGAAGGGGAAGCGGCGGGUAAGGAGGGCCUGCGUUCGGGCGCGUCUGUGACGGGGUUGGGAACUUCCUCUUCUACUCCCUCCGGCUUUCCGGACCCCUGAGGACUGGAGGUAGUAACAGAUUAUGGGCAACAGUCCUUUUAAUUAAUCUACCGUCAUCAUGGCUAAUGAGGACUGUCCCAAGGCUGCUGAUAGUCCUUUUUCAUCAGAUAAACAUGCCCAACUCAUCUUGGCCCAAAUCAAUAAGAUGAGAAAUGGACAGCAUUUCUGUGAUGUGCAGCUGCAAGUUGGACAGGAAAGUUUUAAAGCUCAUCGGCUGGUUUUGGCUGCCAGCAGUCCUUACUUUGCAGCUUUGUUCACUGGAGGAAUGAAAGAGUCCUCAAAAGAUGUUGUACCGAUUCUAGGAAUUGAAGCAGGAAUCUUUCAGAUACUUCUAGAUUUCAUUUACACAGGUAUAGUGAACAUAGGUGUGAAUAAUGUCCAGGAGUUGAUUAUUGCAGCAGACAUGCUACAGUUGACUGAAGUUGUUCAUCUUUGCUGUGAAUUUCUGAAAGGACAAAUUGAUCCACUGAACUGCAUUGGAAUUUUUCAGUUCUCUGAGCAAAUUGCCUGCCAUGAUCUCUUGGAAUUCUCAGAAAACUACAUUCAUGUCCAUUUCUUGGAGGUUCAUAGUGGAGAAGAGUUCCUGGCACUUACGAAAGAUCAGCUGAUCAAAAUUUUGCGAAGUGAAGAGCUUAGCAUUGAGGAUGAAUACCAGGUCUUCUUAGCUGCAAUGCAAUGGAUUCUGAAAGAUUUGGGAAAAAGAAGAAAACAUGUGGUGGAAGUGCUAGACCCAAUUCGAUUCCCUUUAUUACCUCCUCAGAGACUUUUAAAGUAUAUAGAAGGAGUAUCCGAUUUUAAUCUUCGUGUUGCAUUGCAAACACUUCUGAAAGAGUACUGUGAAGUAUGCAAAUCUCCCAAAGAGAACAAGUUUUGUAGUUUUCUGCAGACAUCUAAGGUUCGACCUCGGAAGAAAGCAAGAAAGUACCUGUAUGCAGUAGGUGGAUAUACUCGGUUGCAGGGGGGUCGCUGGAGUGAUAGCAGAGCCCUCAGCUGUGUAGAACGUUUUGACACCUUUAGCCAGUACUGGACCACUGUGUCUUCACUUCAUCAGGCUCGAAGUGGGCUGGGAGUAACAGUUCUGGGAGGGAUGGUCUACGCUAUUGGAGGUGAAAAGGAUUCAAUGAUUUUUGAUUGUACUGAAUGCUAUGAUCCAGUUACUAAACAGUGGACAACUGUAGCUUCGAUGAAUCAUCCCCGCUGCGGCUUAGGAGUGUGUGUGUGUUAUGGGGCUAUCUAUGCUUUGGGUGGAUGGGUUGGAGCUGAGAUAGGGAACACCAUUGAACGAUUUGAUCCUGAUGAAAAUAAAUGGGAAGUAGUUGGUAACAUGGCUGUGUCACGCUACUACUUUGGGUGCUGUGAAAUGCAAGGUUUAAUUUAUGUAAUUGGGGGCAUCAGCAAUGAAGGAAUAGAACUUCGUUCUUUUGAAGUCUAUGAUCCACUUUCUAAGCGUUGGUCUCCACUUCCUCCAAUGGGAACCAGGAGAGCAUAUCUUGGUGUGGCUGCACUCAAUGACUGCAUCUAUUCUGUUGGAGGAUGGAAUGAGACCCAAGAUGCUCUUCAUACUGUAGAAAAAUAUUCCUUUGAAGAGGAAAAGUGGGUUGAAGUUGCCUCAAUGAAAGUGCCUAGAGCAGGCAUGUGUGUUGUGGCAGUCAAUGGUCUUCUGUAUGUUUCUGGAGGUCGAUCUUCCAGCCAUGAUUUUUUGGCUCCAGGUACCUUGGACUCAGUUGAAGUUUAUAACCCUCAUUCAGAUACAUGGACAGAAAUUGGUAACAUGAUCACCAGUCGUUGUGAAGGGGGCGUUGCUGUGCUAUGAAAUAUAAAGCAUAACAGAGCACAAGGAACAUUUUGAAAAUGCAGGACCUGACCUUUUGCAAAGCAAACAUAGAUUUGGUGAUAAGACCCUCUGAUUCUGUGAGUUUUCCAUGUAUUUGGUAGAUAAAUGACUAACGAGGCUGGGCGCAGUGGCCUCAUGCCUAUAAUCCCAGCACUUUGGAAGGCUGAGGCAGAAGGAUCACUUGAGCCCAGGAAUUUGAGGUUGUAGUAAGCUACGAUCAUGCCACUGCACUCCACUCUGGGCAACAGAAUGAGAUCCUGUCUCUUAAAGAAAAAAAAUAAACUCAAGAAUGAUUUUUCUAAAAAUAUGAGUGAGAAUGGAUAUGGAAUAUAUCCCAAUUAAUAAAGAGCUCACACAGAUUUGCCAGGUUUACUAAUAAUAGAAAUGCCAUUUAUGCUGUAGAAUUCUCCAGUUUAAGUGUAGACAACUCCUAUUUUACAAAUUUGUAGAAAUUAUUUACUAGAAGCUUCCUGGCAAAUAGUCCCUUUAGCUACUUCUCCAGUGCAGUAUAAAUUGUAACAUAAAACUUUAUGUGAUAUAGGAAUAGUGUCAAUGACACAGUUUAAAGACCUCUAUAUUCACAAUUAUAUCCAGAGCAUAAUUUUCCAUGGCCAUAGUUUGAGCCACAGAGAAAGCCAAUGAAAUAGAUUCCUACUUUUAUUUAAUGCCAAGAGUUUUCACUAGCCCCAAACUUUUUAUUGGCAGCAGAUAUCCUAGGAGGGGUGUUUGGGAAAUAUCUAGCUAUUUUAAUAGAUAGAUACCUUUUUGCUUGAUGAUAAGUUUUUGCUUGCUCAUAUUUUUUGUCUUGAUCCUGAGAAUGCAAGUAAGGAAUUAAUAGGAGGUUCUUAGUGACCAGAUGUUGUAAUGGGCUAUACAGUCCAGCAGGCAGUAUGCACCUAGAAAUUUCUCCCUUUUUUAGGCUGGGCAUGGUGGCUCACACCUGUAAUCCCAGCACUUUGAGAGGCCGAGGUGAGACGGGAAGAUGGCUUGAACUCAGGAGUUCGAGACUAGCCUGGGCAACGUGAUGAGACUCCGUCUCUACCAAAAAAUAUAUAAAAAUUAGCCGGGCGUUGUGGCUUGUACCUGUGGUCCCAUCUGCUUGGGAGGCUGAGGUUGCAGGAUCACUUGAGCCCAGGAGGUCAAGGCUGCAGUGAGCCAAGAUUGUGCCACUGCACACCGGCCUGGGUGACAGCAUGAGAACCUGUCUCAAAAAAAAAAAAAAAAAAAGAAAAAA